UGCUUGGCGGGCUCUGGGUAGCACGUGCCUGAGACUCCCUGGCUUUUGAGGUCUGCCGAAGCAGGUGACGCCUCUCCUGGGGACACAGAAGCAGUACGGACUCCCAGGUGGCGGUGGUGCUUUCCCUAAGUUCCUACCUCUCUGCCAAAACAAACUAACCAUGUAUUUCUCUGGGGCUUGUCUUCUGAGCUUGCUUUAUAACCAAUUUGAAAUUUCAGGAGACCUGAAACAUAGUUACCUGCUAGCUUUGAUUCCUGAAAUUUCCUUAAAGGGACCACAGUUCUGUUCAGCAAAUGUCUAUCAAAUGUCUGCUACAUGCUAGGGUGCUGACCAGGUGCUAGGGAUACGAGGAUGAAUAAUAGUAUCCCUGCAGAUGAAUUUACUGUCGCUGGGGGAGAGACAGGUCAGACAGGUCAUUUCAAGAAGAGCUUUCCAGUCCAUAUUAAGGGUGAAAGGUUCAGAGAGGUAAGGUUUUCAAGGUCAUUCUUGAUCAAAUAGAAUUGGUCAAGGAAUAUAGAUAACAAACCUCUUCUAAUUGUUCCAGCCAGGAGAGUACAUGGGGUCCUCUGGAGGCAGAGGAGAGAGCGGCUACCCUUGACAUGAUGGUUUUGCCUAGAACUGAUCCUGUUUACCCUUAACUGUGUGGGAAUAAAUAGAAAUAGUUGUUUCUAGAAGUGAUUUUAUCCUGGACAUGCACAUGAGCAUAACUUAGGGAGGACAGAUGGAUGGUAUGUGCAGACCUGAACCAGGCCAUGAAUUCUGUUUUCAUUACAUUUUUUAGUACUACUAAAGCAUCAGCACAUACACAACAUUUAUGCCAUAGCACAAGCCUGUCUUUAAAGUACACUUUACUUUGAGAUGGCUUAAAACUAAUUUCUGCUUGAGCUUUUAUAGAUAAGUACAACUUAUAUUUAUAGCUAAGUAAAACUUUCUUUAGCACUUUUCUUAUAAAGUGUCUGAUGUCUGCCUUUUUGUUUGAAUUUAUAGGCAGAUUCAGUAUGGGUGCUUGACAGUUCAGACAUGAAAUCUGGAUUAUUCUGUAUUUGCGAUUUUAAUAGCAUUAGGCAAUUUACUAUACAUGAAUGGAGGCAUGUUCUCUAGAUAUUUAGGUUCCUUCAUUGUGAACAUUUUUAUAGUUGGUGUCAAACAUUUUUGUUGUACCCCCAGAAACUUAAUCAGUUACUGGUAAUAAGAUCAAUAACUUACCACAAUUUGGGAUACAUACAGUUUUCAGAUUGAGCUGACCUGUGGGCUACCUACUUUGUAAUCAGACCAAGAUCACCAAUAUUUUGGGACUGUUUUAUAGAAAAAAAAAAAAGCACAGGAAAUUAUCUAAAAAUAGAGUAUUGAUUAAGCAGUCUUACUUUGCAUUCAGAUAUAAUUGUCCUUCUUUGCUCUCUGAGGCAUCAUUGCUUCCCUUUUGCACAAUUUCUUUUUCAUUUCCUCUUUGAAAAUACUAAUGGCCCCAUGUGAAAAAAAUGAAAAUAUCUCAGUGUUGUACCACCCAUUGUAUUUUUAAGUCUUUUUAUUUUGAUAAAAAUACACAAUCAUAGGGAACCCCCCACCCCCACCCCAAAUAGCAGUUGAAAUGAAGUGCUUCUAAGUUGUGGAUCAUUAGAAGGGAGCUUUCAGUUGGGCAUGGUGGCUCACGCCUGUAAUCCCAGCACUUUGAGAGGCCAAGACGGGUGGAUCACUUGAGGCCAGCAGUUCGAGACCAGCCUGGCCAACAUAGCAAAACCCCCAUCUCUACUAAAGAUAACAAAAAAUUAGCCGGGUAUGAUGGUACAUGCCUGUAAUCCCAGCUGCUGCGGAGGCUGAGGCAUGAGAAUCGCUUACACCUGGGAGUUGGAGGUUUCAGUGAGCCGAGAUUGCACCACUGUACUCCAUCCAGCCUAGGUGACAGAGUGAAACCCUGUCUCAAAAAAAAAAAAAAAAAGAAAAGGAAAAGGGAGUUUUCAAAAGAGAAAAAAAACUUUUAACUUAACGUGGCAUUUUUGCUCUAUAAAAUAAACAACCAAGGAAAAUAUGUCUGAAUUGGGAGAUAAAAUUUACUUGAUACUCCUUCUUCAUUGGGUUAUCUGUUCAUUCUCUCUGGCUACUCUAGAAAAUGAGUGGCCUGAAAAGGAACAUCCUGCUUGUACAGAUAAGAGAACUGAUAUUGGGGUUUUCUGAUUCCACUUUGGAAUUCAUUGACUUUUUCCUGUUGGUUCUUACAGACAAAAAGUUAUGCCAUUUUUCCCCUCACUUCUCACUUCUCAAUUAGUUUUUAUUAUCUGUAUACUAAAUAUAAGACAUUUCUAAACAUCAGUAAGGCUAAUUUUUAUGGUAAAUUUCAAAAAGAUGUCCUAGAACUAUAUUUUAAUGAAUUGCUCAAAAUGAGUUAAAAAUAUAAAACGCAGUAAUUCAAAAAGGGCAUCCUUAUUUUUGAUUAACUUUAGUUAACUAUGACAUCUAAUUUAGGAAAGUAAAUAGUGUAGUUUUCCACAAUCCAGUUAUAAAAUGCAUUUUUGGGGACCUGCUGUAAACUCAGGCGAGUUAGGUGCAUGUCUUGGCUAUGUCUCCUGCUUCACAGUAGUUGCUCCAGCUCCUUUCUGUUCCCCUCUGUAGGGACCAGCAGCCCCAACUGAGAGUCUCGUCCUUCCUGCCCCAUACCAAGGACUAAUGCAGGCAUCAGGCGUGUUUUCACUUUGGAAAUUUUUAUUACGAAUGGGAGCCAGACUGAUGUUAUCUACUUGUAUUAGUUGAUUUCUUAGUAUUAAGAUUAGAGAAUGCUUGUUUUCUGAGGCAAAAUAAGUAUUUUUAGAUAACCUUUUAUUACAAUUGCUAUUGUUUUAAUCUAAGACUUUUCAAAUAGCUGCUUAGUUUCAAAAAAAAUACUGUUCUAUUAGCUUAUUCAAUUUGUUGGACCAAAUUGUGUUCAUACUACAUUAUCUUUGACUUGAAUAUAGAUACACAGUUGUCCCUUGCUAUCCAUGAGGGAUUAGUUUCAGGACUUCCCUGGGAUACCAAAAUUCACAGAUGCUCAAGUACCUGAUAUAAAAUGGCAUAGUAUUUGCAUGUAACCUAUGCACAUCCUGCCAUGAACUCUUCACAUCAUCUCUAAAUUACUUAUAAUACUUAACACAAUGUAAAUACUAUGUAAAUAGUUGUUAUACUGUACUGCAUAUGAAAUAAUGACCAAAAAAGUCUGUGCAUGUUCAAUACAAAUGCAGUUUUUAAAAAAUAUUUUCAAUCCAUGGUUGGCUGAGUCCAUGGAUGCAAAACCCACAAAUACAGAGGGUCAACUGUAAAUUCUAUCUUAUGUCUAUUAUGAUGACUAAGCAAGCCUGUAGGUCAUUGUGAUGCUGGUAAGCACUUGGCCCUGUUUUAAUUUUUUUCAUUCAUUCAACAGUUACUUUAACUGCCUUUUAUGGGAAACAACAGUGAAUAAAACUGGCACAACCUCUCUGCCCCUGUACCGUCUGCAGUUGAUUUUUCAUUCUUAGGUUUUUAUAAGAUAGUUUUUUUCCUGUUAUUUUUCACUAAUAAGUGAUUUUACAGACUAUGGAAAGUGAAUGCUGUAAAAAUUUACAAAUUAUGCAGAAACACCGAAGUUAUUUCUUAAAAAUGUUCUAAGUAUACUGUUGCCCUUACUUCAAAACUGACUGCCUUCAGUUGGGUUAUCUUAGUAAUAGAUUCUUUCAUAUUAUUCAGAACUCUCUUGUGUUUCAUACAUGUAAAUUACAAUAUUAAGAACUGGUAAGUUUCUUUUUGCAACCUACUUUAUUUACUCUAUAUGGAAAAACCUGUUUUAAGGAAAUUUUUUGACAUCUUCUGAAUUACUUACUAAAGGCAUCUUGUAAGCAUACAGGAGAAUAAAGCUUUGAUGCUUGAUGGUAUUUGCCCUUAAUUAGCAAAAUCUGUUUGACUUUUAAAUAUGAAAUAAUUAUUGAUGCAGGUAAGUGAAAAAAUUCACAGCUCUUAGCAAAAUGAUUAUCAGAACUAUGGAAUUUAAAAUAAGCAGUUUUAAUACAGGCCUGUUCUUUUGCUGGCAUCUCAUAGGAACUGAUUUUAGUAGACCCUCUGAUGUAUGACUCAUUUUGGCUUGUUAGUUUUUUAUAUGAGUCACUGUUUUAGAAUAAUGUAAAACAUCGGAAGAUAAAUCUGGGUGUGUGUGCACAAACACGCCAUACUCUCUCUAUUGUUUCUGUAUGCAAAGUUGCCCUGGAAAAAAUUGCUUCUUCUGGUACCAACAAAAACUAGAAGGGUAUUCUGAACUGCUGUUCAUCUUAGAGUGAUUUGAAAUGGGUGUAUGUAUUUUCUACUUUGGUUCACAGUUCAUCAGACCAAGGCAAAGGAGAAUUUUCGUCACUUGAAAAGCACAAUAACCAAUCUUUGUGAGUUUUUUUUUUUUAAGUAGAAAAGAAAAACAUGAGUACCAAACCAAGUUUUGUUGCACUUUUCAGAAUAGUACUCCUGGUGCUUUUUAAGUUUUUCUUAAUCCUAUACAAGAGAAUAUACAGAUAAUUUUAUCUAACUUUUCAGUUAGGAUUACAUAAAUACAAACUGUAUAUUUUUUAUUAUAUCAAUCCAAAGAAUAAUUUCUAACCAGUCCUGCUUUCUUUUUUGGGGGGAGAUAUUUAGUAGAACUUUGAAAUUAUUUGGCAACUCAUAAGAACUCAAAAUAGGUUCAAUUUAGGGAAAUUAAGAAAUUCAAGAUUAUGUUUUGGGAUAAAAUAAAAUGAUUGGCUGUGUUAUUUUAGACUGUAAAAUACAUAGAAUGGGUGAUUUCUAGACUAUUGGAAUAUGUCACAAUAUACAUAAUUUUAAACUGUGUUGAAAUACUUAGAUGCUAAAGGUUUUUAUUGUAAAAUGUCAUUGAACAAUAAGCAUAAAUAAAGAUUUUAUGAAUGUAUUUGAGAAUGCAAUAAAAUUUAUAUGGAUUGGAGAAUAAAGGAAAAAAUACAUAAACUUAUUGUUUACUAGUUAACUUGGGUUUUCAAUUUGUUUCUACCCAAAUCGUUUUCCACUCAGACAGAUGUAUUAGCUAUUACUUUACAUUAACAGUUGUUUAAAUUAUUUAAAACUGCCUUUAUAAACUGUCUUUUAAACUUUUUAAGUCUUAAAUUUAUUUCCUUUUGGAUAUUUGGCAGCUCUAAAAGAGAAAAUAGGCACUAUCCCCUCUUUUGAUCUUUUAAGGAUAGUGACAGGAUUUAUCCACUUGCAAAUUGGUUUGCUAACCUGCCUUGUCAUAGAAAACAGUAGAAUAAAAGUGAAGUCACAGUUUUAGGGCAUUCAUCCCUUCUUUAUCACACAUAUGCUGUCAAGUUGUUCAUCUUCUGUGGGCCUCUCACCUUAAAAUGGCAAUGAUGGUAAACACAUCCACCUCUCAGAUUCAUUGAAUUCCAGGGAGAUAAUAGAGAUGAAAACACUCCACACGUGUCAGGUAUUUAUAUUCUUAAAAUAACAUAAUACACAAAAUGGUCUUUCAUAUUCGUAAUUACCCUACAAAAAACUCAGUAUGUGCCCUGGGCAAGUAAGUAUUUGCAAAGUUAAUGUUAUUAUUUUGUAAUUUUGAUGUGCAGAAUUCCGUUCUUCCAUUUAUGCAUGUCCUGUGCUUUACAAAAGAAUGGAGCUUUUGCUUUAAUGUUUAAAAUACCUUUAUAGGUCUAAAUUUUUGCUUUUCUUGUCUUUUAAACUAUAAAAAAAUGCUGCUUUCAGAUAUACCCUUGGCAUUUUUAUAAUGAUGCUUGAAUGCCUUCUAUUAAAUACUUUAUUUAGACAUCAUCAAAUUCUUCAAGUAUGAAAGUUUUAUUACAGGGGAUAUUUUUAGAUUUGUGUUAAGAAUCUGAAAGUUAUUUUUAUUUAACCUGUCAUUAACAUAUCUGUUAUUUUAACUGUUUGAUUUAAUUAUCCCUUUAUAAUCAUGAUUUCUGAAUGUUCAUCUUUAAAAUACUCUGAGUUUACUGAUCUCUCAUGCCUUGUGCUCUCUACAAUAGGUGAUUCUAUUCUGCCUUUUGACCGUUAUUCUUUUCAUGUUUACUUGUACGAUCAAGAAUUAACAGAUUGUUUUCUGUGUGUGAUCUCAGUCUACUAAUGAUCAUACUACUGAUAAACAUUAUAAGCUACUUUAAGAGUUUUCAACAAUGACCUCUUAAACCAAAUGAUGCUCUCUUCCUAACACCCCUUUCUUCUGUAGCAAAUCUAUAUUUAACUUCUCUUGCAUGCUUUUGAAAUCUAAAGAGUGCAGAGUUGUUGCUACAUUUCAACCAUCCUUGCAGCAUCCUGAAAAAUAAAUUGGCAGGUGUUGCAGAUAGCAAAAGUGUAGCUCUGAGAGGCCCCCGUUGUGCUAGUGUGCACAGUAUGGGCUGAGUGCUUUCACCGGGAGCCUGUUGUUCUUUGGGUGGCUCCAGAUGUACCCUCCGAAAGGGGCCUAAAAUUGUCACUUCCAUAAUAUUAAUAAACUUAAUAAAAUUUUGAUCAUUUGGUUUAUAAACAGUAGCCCUAAUAUCCAUUUCAGUAGGUAAGUCAGAUUUUAGAAAUAAAUAAAUUUGGGAAAGAAGUGGGGAGUCAUUCAGCAUCACAAAUUGCUAUUUAUCUAGGUAAUACUUUUUAUUUAUGCAUUUAUUUGGUCACGUAAAUGUGCUUAGACCUAAUAAACAUAUGUAGUUGGUGAAAAUUAAUGCAUGACUCGUAAGCAGAGUAUGGAAUGUAAGCAUGUGCCAUGAAACUGCAAUUCUUUUAUCCUGUAUUUUCCAUCAUUUACAUACCGGUUCCAUUUAGAGGAUAGUCCAUUUUCACUUUUUUUUCAUAGAUUGGCCAAAAUGGGAAGGAUUGGAUUCCACUCUCUUCCACGAAGAGUCAAUGGGACUGGCUAAGAUCAAAGUCUGAGGCUUUUUCCAUCAGUAAUCAGUCCCUUUUUGCUUUCUUUUACGACCACAUGAAACUUGAGAAGCCACCUAAAGCUAUAUCAUUUAGUGGAGUUGGGCAGUUCCCAAGUGUCCAACAAGAAGGCCUGGUUUAGGCUGCGAUGGCCACUGUCAUUCCUGGUGAUUUGUCAGAAGCACAUGGCUACUCAUUCUCCUGAGAAAACCCACAAGUGUAAUUAUUGUGAGAAAAUGUUUCACCGGAAAGAUCAUCUGAAGAAUCACCUCCAUACACACGACCCUAACAAAGAGACGUUUAAGUGCGAAGAAUGUGGCAAGAACUACAAUACCAAGCUUGGAUUUAAACGUCACUUGGCCUUGCAUGCCGCAACAAGUGGUGACCUCACCUGUAAGGUAUGUUUGCAAACUUUUGAAAGCACGGGAGUGCUUCUGGAGCACCUUAAAUCUCAUGCAGGCAAGUCGUCUGGUGGGGUUAAAGAAAAAAAGCACCAGUGCGAACAUUGUGAUCGCCGGUUCUACACCCGAAAGGAUGUCCGGAGACACAUGGUGGUGCACACUGGAAGAAAGGACUUCCUCUGUCAGUAUUGUGCACAGAGAUUUGGGCGAAAGGAUCACCUGACUCGACAUAUGAAGAAGAGUCACAAUCAAGAGCUUCUGAAGGUCAAAACAGAACCAGUGGAUUUCCUUGACCCAUUUACCUGCAAUGUGUCUGUGCCUAUAAAAGACGAGCUCCUUCCGGUGAUGUCCUUACCUUCCAGUGAACUGUUAUCAAAGCCAUUCACAAACACUUUGCAGUUAAACCUCUACAACACUCCAUUUCAGUCCAUGCAGAGCUCGGGAUCUGCCCACCAAAUGAUCACAACUUUACCUUUGGGAAUGACAUGCCCAAUAGAUAUGGACACUGUUCAUCCCUCUCACCACCUUUCUUUCAAAUAUCCGUUCAGUUCUACCUCAUAUGCAAUUUCUAUUCCUGAAAAAGAACAGCCAUUAAAGGGGGAAAUUGAGAGUUACCUGAUGGAGUUACAAGGUGGCGUGCCCUCUUCAUCCCAAGAUUCUCAAGCAUCGUCAUCAUCUAAGCUAGGGUUGGAUCCUCAGAUUGGGUCCCUAGAUGAUGGUGCAGGAGACCUCUCCCUAUCCAAAAGCUCUAUCUCCAUCAGUGACCCCCUAAACACACCAGCAUUGGAUUUUUCUCAGUUGUUUAAUUUCAUACCUUUAAAUGGUCCUCCCUAUAAUCCUCUAUCAGUGGGGAGCCUUGGAAUGAGCUAUUCCCAGGAAGAAGCACAUUCUUCUGUUUCCCAGCUCCCCCCACAAACACAGGAUCUUCAGGAUCCUGCAAACACUAUAGGGCUUGGGUCUCUGCACUCACUGUCAGCAGCUUUCACCAGCAGUUUAAGCACAAGUACCACCCUCCCACGUUUCCAUCAAGCUUUUCAGUAGGAUUCUGGGACAUGGAUUCAUUACAGAAAUGUAUGUGUAGCUGUGCCCUAGAUGACCAUUUUUAUUUUAGUGCCUACUUUAAAACAGUAUAAAAAUUUCUGCUUUUGUAUAAUACAAAUUUUCAUUAAGCCAGUAUAAAAUAGAAACUAGCUUUUAAACUGAGCUUUGGAACCAUUUGUGUUCAGUUAAGUUUACCUGGGUAUUUUGUCCUGAUUCACUGCCAAUUGUCACAUUUUAAGACUUUUUUUUUUCCAUAUAGGAAAGCCAUUAUUAGUAGUAAACUUUUACAAAUCCCAUUUUCAAAUUACUUUUAGAUCUUAAAAUUUUCAUUUUUGUCUAAUAACAGUGGCUCUACCUUUUGACAUCUGGCUCAUUAAAAAAUUUAGCAAUAGAAUGUAAAUUGUAUAAAAAGUUUGUGAAUAACUCAAGGGUUUAAAUUUUCUUACUAGCUUCUAAAUGGAUUAAUAAUCAAGUGCUUCAAAUGAAUUAAGAGUCCAGUUUCGGAAGAUAAUAAAUGUUUGUUAGAUACACCAUAAUUUCAGAUCAGUAUAUUCUGAAGACUCCCUGUUGUCUGGCUAAAAUAUUUGCCAUCUUUAUUAUGAGCCUUUAAGGAAAACAAACCCUAAACACAAAGCAUCAGUAUUUAUAGCAAAAAGAGACUCUGUUAGGUGACAUGGCAUUUCGUGUCACUUAAUAGUUGGCCCUAAAUUAGUACACAGGAUAUUUUGUCGUGUUUCAUCCUUCUUAACAUGCUAUCUUUUCAUUUAAUAAUAGUAAUAGUGUAUGGCAUUGGGGUCUUCAGAGUCGAUAUAUAGGUAGAUCUCUUUAGUCUUUUCCACCUUUCACAUCCAAGGGGUGGGUCAAGUGCAGCCAGCAAUUUAUUUUCAUUGUUGGCCCACGGUUAGUCCAUAAUCUAGAGCCAUUGUGGAACUGCAGCCAUGAGGUGUGUUUAUCCCACAGUGGAUUGACUCAGCCUCUGUGGGUGACAGACUUCUAAGCAGGAAGAUAGACGUGAAGCACAUGGUUACAUUUGGGAACUUGUGUAGGGAUCAUGGCCCCUGUAGCCAGGGUUAAAAACUGGACUUUUUAGAAGUAAAGUAAAAGCAUAUCGCUUAUAUCAUUUCUUGCUGAAUUUGAUAUGUUUUUCUUUCCCUUAAGAAUCAAAAGCAGAAAACAAAAACAACAGUCCUACUCCGAUGUUAUCUUUCUGAUUCAAUGUGAAUCCAUCUUUCCUUGCAAUAUUUUGGAUGGAGAAUUUGAAGUUAAAUGCAUUAGAAAACUACCUGAUGAACUACCACAAAGUUUUAAGUGACUAGAAAUAUAUACAGUAAAAUCCCACUUUCAUGCAUCUCUGGGAAAUGAUAGGAGUAUUGCAAAUAAGUUGAGUUUGUAGAGGGUAACAAAGUAAAGUAAAACAAACCUAUCUUGGUUAACAUGAAAAUAACAAUUGAGAAUAUAUUAUAUUCACUGAAUAAUUAUAGGCUUUUCCUCACAUUAGACAACCAACAUAAUCUUCUUAAAGGUCUAAUUAAUAUAUUUUUCUAAGGGUCAGUUGGGACAUUAACCUAAGAAACAUAUCUAUUAAGCACUUGUUAACACCUUAUUUUAGGACCCUUUCCGUUGGGGAUGGGGGCAAGGGUGGGAGGUUUUUAGAAGAGUAUAUAUCUCUUUAAAAAAAAACAGAAAGAAAAAUAUUUCUGAGCACUCAUUAGCCCUAUAUGGAAACUUCUUUCCUUUUUGUAGGGCCAGUUAUCACUGCAGAUUGCAAUGUUUACCAAGAAUUUCUAAAAAUGAGUGCAGAUUACUGAAUAUAAUACAUUAUUUAAAAUAUUUGGGAGUAGUAUAAUUUGUGGAGAAAUGUAAAUUGUAAUAAUGUAAAUGGGGGCUUCAAUAUAUAUAUAUAAUACACACACACACACACAUGCACACAUACCGCACUUCAUAGAAUCAAAGUUGCUCUCUGAAGGAGCUUUGGCUCCUGAUAUUUUAUCAUGCUCCUAUAUUUUUUUAAUCCUUGGAGCAGUAGUUUUUAUACUUAUGUAUUUAAAUUUUAUUAUGAAAAAUUACAUUUAUUAAAAAAGUGUGUUCCAAAGGCAUUAAAAUUAUAUAUGUUAAUAAGGAAGUACAUUUUUAAAUUUUUCAAACUGCUCCUAGCUUUUGAUUAGGAGAAUAUUUUUUCUGAAAGUAGGCUUUUCGCUCUGCUUCAUUACUGCUUCCUUUAGUUUCUAUGAAACAGAUUGCUUACCUAAAUCUUUAGUUGAAUGAUUAGUGUUCAAUAUUGCUUUAAUCACCAUAUAAAAGGAAAAAAAUUGGUGACAGAGCACAAAUAGAAAACCUAUUUUUAAAUAGAAAUCACAAAUAGCAAGUGUGGAAGCACUACUUUAUUCUGUUUAAAAUGUACUUAAGAAGUCAUCAAAUUAGUGAACUGAGACAUUGGCCUUAGUAGGCUGUAUUCACUGCUAAUUUAAAAAAGGGAGUACCAGGAUUUAUUAAGUAAAGCAUUUUGGAAAUGGGGAAUAGCGCCAUAUAUGUAUGUAUGUGUAUGUGUGUGUGUGUGUGUGUAUAUAUACACACACACACACAUACUUAAAUCUUGCCCUGCAUGAAAUUCAAAUACAUGGAGGCACAUCUUCAGGGCACCAGUGUUAAAAUUUUGGAGUCUUAAUUUUCAUGUGUACACCUCUUUGCCUGUUCCCACCCCCAGACUUGAAAUAACACUUCAGAGUAAGAGGGAAUUCAGCUAAUUUGUUUUUAAAAUUGACUGUAGUGGUCACUAAACCCUUUUUGAGAGAAUUUCUAUUAAAGAUGAGGCAGACUCGCUUAUUUGAAUUGCACAAUGUUCUAACAAGGAUGUAACACAGAAUUGGCUUUUUUUUCCCUAGAAAAAGAUUGUUUGUUUCUAUGUCAACUAGAUAUGAUUAAAAAUAAGUAUUGCCAAUGCUGUUUUCAUUCUCUAGUGGCCAGAAUCAUUAUCCUUGAAAUUUCUGGUAGUGCCUUAGCUUGGUUAAAAAAAAAAAAAAAAAAAAAAAAAAGGGAUUAACAUUAAAUAAAAGUAGUUUAGAAUUUGGGCCUCAGACAAGAUAUUGAACCUCAUUCAGUUUCACUUCCACAUGUAUGUACAAGUUAGGUCACCAAACACGGAAGUGUGAGUGUGGAAGGAUCUUGGCACUGUAAGCAAUGCUAUCCAUUGAUGUAUACAAGUACCUUUAUAGUUAUCGAUCACUGUUAAAACUUUCAUUUUAAAAUCCUAUUACCAAGUUCAGUUUUUUAAAACUUCAAUUGUCCUGGCUGAUUAUGCAUCACUCUGUGUGCAACUUUUUUAUUUCAUUUAGUGUUUCUUUCAAGCUGUGUAUUUUUGCCUAUUUGUUGCUUGUGCUUUAUUUUUCUUAGUCAUUUGUGGAAUAUAGUGAUAUAUUGUGUUAAUUUGGACAGUAGCGGUUUUUAAAAACCAUAUACUGACUGAAACAUGAGCCAGAGCCGAUUGCUUUAUUAAGCUAAUAAUGAAUGUUAAAGAGUACAUAUUUUCAGGAUCGUUCAUCUAGUGAGCAAUACACAUAUUAUAGGCCAAUAUUUUUUUAAAAAAUAGAGCUUGGUCAACCUCUAUACUACACAUAUUACAAGAUAUAGCACUUUCAAAAUGAAUCUAAACCUUUACAGAAACUUUCUUAUAGGUUAUGCCUUUUAUUUUAAGACUUAUUAUAAUUCAAGUGCCAUUAGAUGAUAUAUAUGUAGGCCUUUGAUAUAUAAUGCUUUGUGUACAAAAAUGGUAGAUGGUAUUUUAAACAGGUACAUUUUUACAGUGUUUUCUUAUCAAUUUGCUAUAUUGCACAGAAUCAGUGUGUGUCUUUUCAUAAGGUUUUACAAUGGUUUAUUUUUUUACAAGGUUUACGUGUCUCAAAGCACACUGUCUUCCCAGUACGUAAGUUAAAAAAUACCAGUUCACCCAAGUUGCUUCUAGCCUACUGAGAUCCAUGUGACAUUGGAGGAGAUCUUUUAAAUGUUUAGUAUUCGUCAUUAGCAAUGGCUGGCUGUUAGUUCUGGUAAAUGUGUGCCUAAGUUGAAUUUGUCUUGUUUUUCUCACACUGUGUCAGCAGCCAUGUCUACAACACAGAUAAGUCUGUUGUGAUCACAUAGAUCUACAUAAGUUGUGCAGUUUUGUGCUAAAAACCCAUAGGGAGCUCCUUUGGGAUCAUAGAAAAGAAGAUCAUGCAACCAGCAUUGGUGAAGGCACACUCAGAUUGCACUUAGGGCCUUUCUAUGAUGUUGUCAACCCUCUGAGGAUGGAAGGCAGUGUCUUUUGAUGUUAUCUAGCCUAGAAAUGACACAGAACUAUUGCUAAUGUAUAAAACACUUCAUUAUAUAAGCUUCAGUGGUACAGAUGAACCAGAAUGAAUGUUUAUCUUCUCAGAAACACUCCUUCAAUAUUAUAUUGGAUCAUGCUGCUAAUGUAACUUGGGCUACAACUCUUCAUGGUGCUACAAACUUCUCUGUCUCAUUCAGUCGUAUUUUUUUAUCCAUAGAAAAAGGACUACAUUAGGUGUAAAAGUGUACAAUAUAUUUUUAUACUGUGACUUAAUUUGUCAUUAACAAACUUUUACACCACCACAAUGUAUUCAUGUGCACUUGCAAAAGGAGAUCUCGGACAUGCAAAUGUUACCAGAACAAACCCAGCUUUUGUCCACAAGGUGACUGUAACUCAGAAUGGAAAGUGGGCUUUAUAAUAGGGUGUGGAGUGAAGAACAUGCUGUAUGUUACUAACAGCCCUUUGAAUUUAACAAAAACUGGGAAUCCAUUAGGAAACGGAUUGCAUCAUACCUGAACAUAAGCUGGACUGCUGAAAUUGUAUUUUUAGCUAAUGAAAAAGUGUUUGGACUAGUACUCUAAAAAUGUUCUAAUGAUAAAGUUUUGAGUCAAAAUAGAAAAGAAAAAAAUCUGCAUUCCAGGCCGAAUUUUGUAUAUUUUUAUUGCAUUUAAAAUUGCUAUUCUGUAAUAUUGGGAAAUCAAGUGGCUUAUCAUGUAUAUCGUGUACUUAAAAUGUAUUCACAAACUACUGUUGUAUUUGUAUAAAAUAUAGACAAAGAUCAUAUUUUUUGUGUGUGUAUAAGCUCUGUAAAAUAGCAAUCACAUUAUGAAGCUGCAGUGAUACUACAUUUUAAACAUUCACAUCCAAAGAAGCAGACUAUUUAUUGUCCAUAUACCAGAUUUAAAAUAUUAAUUUGCUGCUAAUUAAAUAAUAGUACUGCAGCUUCUUGUGGCCUACAGUGUUAUGUUUGCUGUAAGAAUAAGAUAUGUGAAUUCCACAAAAUAUAUGAAUAAAAUUAUAGAAUGGCUUUA